ACGGUGCACUCUGGGAGCUGUCACUAGGCCCUUCGGCUCCCGGUCUCGGUGUAGCUGCCGUGGUUGCCAGGAGAGCUGCGCCGGCGAGAAGCGGCCGAGCCAGCAGCAGGAAGGAACACACAAGUAGUUAUCUUUCAGGCUGUCUUUGAAUACUUCCAUGACCCUGAACACUAGCUGAGGAGAGUUUCAACCACUGCUAACAGUAAUGACUUUACAUGAGUUUGGAACUGGUCUCUAGUGGGAAGUUGUGGGAGGAUGAACACAGAAGAGCUGGAGUUAUUGAGUGACUCCAAAUACAGAAACUAUGUAGCAGCAAUUGACAAAGCACUAAAGAAUUUUGAAUACUCCAGUGAAUGGGCAGAUUUGAUAUCAGCACUUGGAAAACUUAAUAAGGUUUUACAAAAUAAUGCAAAGUACCAAGUAGUACCCAAAAAGCUGACCAUAGGCAAACGCCUAGCUCAAUGUCUACAUCCAGCAUUACCAGGUGGAGUUCAUCGGAAGGCGCUUGAAACAUAUGAAAUUAUCUUCAAAAUAAUUGGACCUAAGCGACUUGCCAAAGAUCUUUUUUUAUAUAGUUCUGGAUUAUUUCCUCUUCUUGCAAAUGCUGCCAUGUCUGUGAAACCAACAUUGCUCAGUUUGUAUGAGAUAUAUUAUCUGCCUUUGGGUAAAACACUGAAACCUGGUCUACAGGGAUUGCUUACUGGUAUUCUUCCUGGCUUAGAAGAAGGAUCAGAGUACUAUGAGAGAACAAAUAUGUUGUUGGAAAAGGUUGCUGCUGCUGUGGACCAGUCAGCAUUCUACAGUGCCCUGUGGGGUAGUCUUCUCACCAGUCCUGCUGUGCGUUUACCUGGAAUCACGUAUGUUCUUGCCCAUUUAAACAGGAAGCUUUCUAUGGAAGAUCAACUUUAUAUAAUUGGCAGUGAUAUUGAGCUAAUGGUAGAAGCAGUAAGUACUUCAGUGCAGGACUCAAGUGUACUUGUACAGAGAAGCACACUGGACCUCAUACUCUUCUGUUUUCCAUUCCACAUGAGUCAGGCCACUCGACCGGAUAUGAUCAGGAUCUUGUCAGCAGCCCUUCAUGUAGUGCUAAGGAGGGAUAUGUCUCUGAAUCGAAGACUUUAUGCAUGGCUUCUUGGUUUUGAUAACAACGGUGCUAUCAUAGGACCCAGAAGCACAAGACACAGUAAUCCUGAAGAACAUGCCACUUACUAUUUCACUACCUUUUCAAAAGAAUUAUUAGUCCAGGCAAUGGUGGGAAUCUUACAAGUGAAUGGAUUUGGAGAAGAGAACACUCUAAUGCAGGAUCUAAAGCCUUUUCGCAUUUUAAUCAGUUUACUGGACAAACCUGAGCUAGGACCUGUAAUUCUAGAAGAUGUCCUGAUUGAAGUGUUUAGAACAUUAUAUUCUCAAUGCAAAGCAGAGUUGGAUCUUCAAACUGAACCACCCUUCAGCAAGGAUCAUGCUCAGUUAAGCAGUAAAUUAAGAGAAAAUAAGAAAACAGCAGAGCUGAUUAAAACUGCUAACCUUCUCUUUAAUUCCUUCGAACCUUAUUAUAUGUGGGAUUAUGUUGCACGCUGGUUUGAAGAAUGUUGUAGGAGGACACUGCAUGUGAGACUUCAGAUUGGACCUGGAGAUAGUAAUGACUCAUCUGAAUUACAGCUGACCAAUUUCUGCUUACUGGUGGAUUUUUUGUUGGACAUAGUUUCUUUGCCUACUAGAAGUAUGAGGGUGCUGUGUCAGGAGACUUACAUUGAAAUCCAGACAGAACACUUGCCCCAGUUGCUGCUCAGAAUGAUUUCUGCCUUGACAAGCCAUCUCCAGACAUUGCACUUAUCUGAACUCACAGAUUCUCUCAGACUCUGCUCAAAGAUCCUUAGCAAGGUUCAGCCUCCACUGUUAUCUGCUAGCACUGGAGGUGUUUUGCAGUUUCCAAGUGGGCAGAACAAUUCAGUCAAAGAGUGGGAAGACAAAAAGGUAUCAUCAGUUUCUCAUGAAAAUCCUACUGAAGUGUUUGAAGAUGGAGAAAAUCCACCAAGUAGUCGAUCAUCAGAGAGUGGAUUCACUGAGUUUAUACAAUAUCAAGCAGACCGAACUGAUGAUAUUGACAGAGAACUGAGUGAGGGCCAGGGGGCAGCUGCCAUCCCAAUUGGUAGCACAUCCUCUGAGACAGAAACAGCAUCCACUGUGGGAUCUGAAGAAACCAUCAUCCAGACCCCUUCCGUAGUCACUCAGGGGACAGCAACCCGAAGUAGGAAGACAGCCCAAAAGACUGCAAUGCAGUGCUGCUUGGAGUAUGUCCAACAGUUUCUUACCAGACUUAUCAACCUCUACAUCAUUCAGAAUAACUCUUUUUCUCAGUCUUUGGCUACAGAACAUCAAGGGGAUCUUGGUCGAGAACAAGGAGAGACUUCAAAAUGGGACAGAAAUUCACAAGGAGAUGUAAAAGAGAAAAACAUAAGUAAACAAAAAACUUCUAAAGAAUACCUGUCUGCCUUCCUUGCUGCCUGUCAGCUCUUCCUAGAGUGCUCAAGUUUCCCAGUUUACAUUGCUGAGGGGAACCAUACAUCAGAGUUACGUUCUGAAAAAUUGGAGACUGACUGUGAGCAUGUGCAGCCUCCACAGUGGCUCCAGACUCUGAUGAAUGCUUGCAGCCAAGCAAGUGAUUUCAGUGUUCAGAGUGUUGCUAUUUCACUAGUUAUGGACCUGGUGGGACUGACACAGUCUGUGGCCAUGGUCACUGGGGAAAACAUCAACAGUGUAGAGCCUGCACAACCCUUAAGUCCAAACCAGGGAAGAGUAGCUGUGGUUAUUAGACCUCCCCUCACUCAGGGCAAUCUGAGGUACAUAGCUGAGAAGACUGAAUUUUUCAAGCAUGUAGCUUUAACAUUGUGGGACCAGUUGGGAGAUGGGACACCUCAGCAUCACCAGAAGAGUGUGGAACUAUUUUAUCAAUUACAUAACUUAGUUCCUUCUUCUAGCAUCUGUGAGGAUGUUAUAAGUCAGCAGUUAACCCAUAAAGAUAAGAAAAUAAGGAUGGAAGCACAUGCCAAGUUUGCAGUUCUUUGGCAUCUAACGAGAGAUCUCCAUAUAAAUAAAUCUUCAUCUUUUGUACGUUCUUUUGACAGGUCACUGUUCAUCAUGUUAGAUAGCCUUAACAGUCUCGAUGGUUCUACUAGCUCUGUGGGACAAGCCUGGCUGAACCAAGUCCUACAAAGACAUGAUAUUGCACGAGUUUUGGAACCAUUGCUAUUGCUCCUGCUUCAUCCAAAAACUCAGAGGGUUUCAGUACAGCGUGUACAAGCAGAACGUUAUUGGAAUAAGUCUCCCUGUUAUCCAGGAGAGGAGAGUGACAAGCAUUUCAUGCAAAAUUUUGCCUGCAGCAAUGUGAGCCAAGUACAACUCAUCACAUCAAAAGGAAAUGGUGAAAAGCCACUUACCAUGGAUGAAAUAGAGAACUUUAGUCUCACUGUGAAUCCAUUAAGUGACAGACUUUCCCUCCUAAGUACCAGCAGUGAGACAAUUCCAAUGGUUGUGUCUGAUUUUGAUCUUCCAGACCAACAGAUAGAAAUACUUCAGAGUUCUGACUCGGGAUGUUCACAGUCCUCUGCUGGGGACAACUUGAGUUACGAAGUUGAUCCUGAAACCGUGAAUGCCCAAGAGGAUUCUCAAAUGCCCAAGGAAAGCUCCCCAGAUGAUGAUGUUCAACAGGUAGUAUUUGACCUGAUAUGUAAAGUUGUAAGUGGCCUCGAAGUGGAAUCUGCAUCAGUUACAUCUCAAUUAGAAAUUGAAGCUAUGCCCCCAAAGUGCAGUGAUAUAGAUCCAGAUGAAGAGACGAUUAAAAUUGAAGAUGACUCCAUUCAACAGAGUCAGAAUGCUUUGCUGAGUAAUGAAAGUUCUCAGUUUCUGUCUGUGUCUGCAGAGGGAGGCCAUGAGUGUGUGGCAAAUGGAAUCUCCAGGAAUAGCUCCUCACCUUGUAUUUCAGGAACCACACACACUCUUCAUGACUCUUCUGUUGCUUCCAUAGAAACCAAAUCUAGACAAAGGAGUCACAGUAGUAUUCAAUUCAGCUUCAAAGAAAAAUUAUCAGAAAAAGUUUCGGAGAAGGAAACAAUAGUUAAGGAGUCAGGUAAACAACCAGGAGCAAAACCUAAAGUAAAACUUGCCAGAAAAAAGGAUGAUGACAAGAAAAAAUCUUCAAAUGAAAAACUCAAACAAACCAGUGUAUUCUUCAGUGAUGGUCUGGAUUUAGAGAACUGGUAUAGCUGUGGAGAGGGAGACAUUUCUGAAAUUGAGAGUGACAUGGGUUCUCCAGGAUCUCGAAAAUCUCCCAAUUUCAACAUUCAUCCUCUCUAUCAACAUGUGCUCCUGUAUCUCCAGUUGUAUGAUUCAUCCAGGACUUUGUAUGCUUUCUCUGCCAUCAAAGCCAUCUUGAAAACUAACCCUAUAGCUUUUGUAAAUGCCAUUUCAACUACUAGUGUAAAUAAUGCAUAUACUCCUCAGUUGUCUCUCCUUCAGAAUCUAUUGGCCAGACACCGGAUUUCUGUUAUGGGCAAAGAUUUUUAUAGUCACAUUCCAGUGGACUCAAAUCAUAACUUCCGGAGUUCUAUGUACAUAGAAAUUCUUAUUUCUCUCUGCUUAUAUUACAUGCGUAGCCAUUACCCAACUCAUGUCAAGGUUACUGCACAAGAUUUAAUAGGCAAUCGAAACAUGCAAAUGAUGAGCAUAGAAAUUCUGACACUACUCUUCACUGAGCUGGCAAAAGUAAUAGAAAGCUCAGCGAAGGGUUUCCCUAGUUUUAUUUCUGAUAUGUUAUCUAAGUGCAAAGUUCAGAAAGUGAUUCUUCAUUGUUUGCUGUCAUCUAUCUUUAGUGCUCAGAAAUGGCAUAGUGAAAAAAUGGCAGGUAAGAACCUGGUUGCUGUGGAAGAAGGUUUCUCAGAGGACAGCCUUAUUAAUUUCUCAGAGGAUGAAUUUGACAAUGGCAGCACGUUGCAGUCACAACUUCUUAAGGUGCUUCAGAGGCUGAUUGUUCUAGAACACAGAGUAAUGACUAUUCCUGAAGAGAAUGAAACAGGUUUUGAUUUUGUUGUAUCUGACUUAGAACACAUCAGUCCCCAUCAACCCAUGACUUCUCUUCAGUAUUUGCAUGCUCAGCCAAUCACAUGUCAAGGCAUGUUCCUCUGUGCAGUGAUACGAGCUUUGCAUCAGCACUGUGCAUGUAAGAUGCACCCACAAUGGAUUGGUUUAAUCACAUCUACUCUGCCUUACAUGGGAAAAGUUCUGCAGAGAGUGGUUGUUUCUGUGACACUACAACUGUGCAGAAAUUUAGAUAAUCUAAUUCAGCAGUACAAAUACGAAACAGGAUUAUCUGAUAGUAGGCCUCUGUGGAUGGCAUCAAUUAUUCCACCAGAUAUGAUUCUUACUCUUUUGGAAGGGAUUACAGCCAUUAUCCAUUACUGUUUGUUGGAUCCAACUACACAGUAUCACCAACUUUUGGUCAGUGUAGACCAGAAACACUUGUUUGAAGCACGCAGUGGAAUCCUCUCAAUCCUUCAUAUGAUCAUGUCCUCUGUGACACUGCUUUGGAGCAUACUGCAUCAAGCUGAUUCUUCAGAAAAGAUGACUAUUGCCGCAUCCGCAUCUCUUACCACUAUUAAUCUUGGAGCUACAAAGAACUUGAGACAACAGAUUCUUGAAUUGUUGGGCCCCAUUUCAAUGAAUCAUGGUGUUCACUUUAUGGCUGCCAUUGCAUUUGUGUGGAAUGAAAGAAGACAGAAUAAAACAACCACCAGGACCAAGGUCAUUCCUGCAGCCAGUGAAGAACAGCUUUUAUUAGUGGAAUUGGUUCGUUCAAUCAGUGUCAUGAGAGCAGAAACUGUUAUCCAGACUGUAAAAGAAGUUUUAAAGCAGCCACCAGCCAUAGCCAAGGACAAGAAACAUCUUUCUUUGGAAGUCUGCAUGCUUCAGUUUUUCUAUGCUUAUAUUCAAAGGGUUCUGAAUGAGUUUAUUAUGAAAAACCCUAGUUUGGAAAAUAAAAAAGACCAAAGAGACCUUCAGGAUGUAACUCACAAAAUAGUGGAUGCAAUUGGUGCAAUUGCUGGUUCUUCUCUGGAACAGACAACAUGGCUGCGACGAAAUCUUGAAGUUAAGCCUUCUCCCAAAAUAAUGGUAGAUGGAACCAAUUUGGAAUCUGAUGUUGAAGAUAUGUUAUCACCUGCAAUGGAAACCGCAAACAUAACUCCUUCUGUAUAUAGUGUCCAUGCAUUGACAUUACUCUCUGAGGUUUUGGCUCAUCUUUUGGAUAUGGUUUUCUAUAGUGAUGAAAAGGAGCGGGUUAUUCCUUUACUUGUAAAUAUUAUGCAUUAUGUUGUGCCCUACCUCAGAAAUCACAGUGCACAUAAUGCCCCUAGUUAUCGAGCUUGUGUCCAGCUGCUCAGCAGUCUUAGUGGGUAUCAGUACACACGGAGAGCUUGGAAAAAAGAAGCUUUUGACCUCUUUAUGGAUCCCAGUUUCUUUCAGAUGGAUGCCUCUUGUGUUAAUCAUUGGAGAGCAAUUAUGGACAAUCUGAUGACACAUGAUAAAACAACAUUUAGAGAUUUGAUGACUCGUGUAGCAGUGGCUCAAAGCAGUUCACUUAAUCUCUUUGCAAACCGUGAUGUGGAGCUAGAACAGAGAGCUAUGCUUCUUAAAAGAUUAGCAUUUGCUAUUUUUAGCAGUGAAAUUGACCAGUACCAGAAAUAUCUUCCAGAUAUACAAGAGAGAUUGGUUGAGAGUCUCCGUUUGCCACAGGUGCCAACUCUCCAUUCUCAAGUGUUCCUGUUUUUCAGAGUGUUACUUUUAAGAAUGUCUCCCCAACAUCUUACCUCACUCUGGCCUACCAUGAUUACAGAACUUGUACAAGUAUUUUUACUGAUGGAGCAGGAACUCACUGCUGAUGAAGAUAUUUCACGGACUUCAGGGCCCUCUGUGGCUGGUCUGGAGACAACGUACACAGGAGGUAAUGGCUUCUCUACUUCAUAUAACAGCCAGCGGUGGUUAAACCUCUAUCUCUCUGCUUGCAAAUUUUUGGAUUUGGCUCUCGCAUUGCCCUCUGAAAACCUUCCUCAGUUUCAGAUGUACCGAUGGGCCUUUAUUCCAGAAGCCUCAGAUGAUUCAGGUUUGGAAGUCAGAAGGCAGGGUAUACAUCAACGAGAAUUUAAACCUUACGUGGUACGACUAGCAAAACUUCUUCGGAAAAGAGCAAAGAAAAAUCCAGAGGAAGACAACUCAGGGAGAACAUUGGGUUGGGAGCCAGGGCACUUGCUGCUCACCAUCUGCACCGUGCGCAGUAUGGAGCAGCUCCUGCCGUUCUUCAAUGUGCUCAGUCAAGUCUUCAACAGCAAAGUCACAAGCCGAUGUGGAGGACACUCAGGGAGUCCUAUCCUCUACUCAAAUGCCUUCCCUAAUAAGGACAUGAAACUGGAGAACCACAAACCAUGUUCCAGCAAAGCCAGGCAAAAAAUAGAAGAGAUGGUAGAAAAAGAUUUUCUGGAAGGGAUGAUAAAAACUUGAGCACCAUUGCUGGUUCCAUUUAGCUUACAUGUAAAUGUAAUUAUUUAAAACACACACACUGCUCUGCGUUGUAUAGUUUUUCCUUUUUUGUAUGUAACAGAACACAUUUCAGAUUGUAUUUAAUUUAAAUAUUUGUAUAUAAGAGCAAAUGUCUGAAUGUGGCCUGAAUCAAGUUUAAAUAUUGUUGGCUCAUACUGAUUAUGGUGCCUAAGAGAGCUAUAUAUAUACACAUGUAAAGUCCAUUGUUUUUAUUGUCCUGAGUUGUCUUAAACCUGCAAAAUAUACACUACCCAUUUUUUUUUUCCAUUGGUUUCAGACUUGGUUCAAUUAAGAUUGGUUGGGGAUUUUUCUCUUUUCCUUAUUAACCAUGUUCUGGUAUCAGAAUGGUGUUCCUUCUCCAUCAGAGGCUGGGAAACGUAUUAUAAUUAGUUUUUCUCCCACAUACCUUCACCAAGAGCAGUGAAGAAUAACUGAAGGCUGGACCAUGCAUCCUUAAAAGUAUUGCAUGAGCAUCUCCACCUCAGUAUGGAAGAGGGAUGGACAACCCCCUAUUCAUACCUCUGAGUUCCUGAUGGCAUUAGUCAUAUAGGUAAGUCAUCUAAUAAUCUUUCUUAAGACUCUGCAAUGGAAAAACUGGUUGUAUAAAGUCUUCUCUGCCCUCUCCAUUUGUAUCAGCAAUGGGGAAUGCUGCAAAACAUCAUCUUGCUCAUGUGAUGGUGAUGGCAAAGAUAUCACAAGGAGUUGGUAAUAAGAUUUAAUUUUCCAGUAGCCUGCAUGAAUUGUUCCCCACAUAAAACUGUACAGUUAGUGACUGAAUUGUAUACUUAAGUCCCAGUAUUUUACAUUAGUGAGACUGAAAUUAGAGGUAAAUUUCUUUAACAAGUGUAAGGCUUACCUAUUUAUAAAGAAUUAUUCUGUUAGUGUUUAAGAAAAACAGAUCUAGAGACAAUCCAGUAGGCUGCAUUGUAAACAUUAUGAUUAUAAAUCUCUUAGUACUGCCAUUAUUAUUGACAGUUUUGUAAAGACUUGUAAAAAGUCCAGUUUCUCAGGAAUAUGAAAAUUAUCUUCAGAAACCUGGUUGGGGCCUUUCUCCAAUUCCUCCAGCCAGCUGAAAUACUGCCAAGCUCACUUCAUGUGCAAGGUGAUCUGCACUUUCCUGCAAAUUACAUUAAAAGAGAUUAGAUGAGAAAGACAUAGCAUGUGUCUAACAUGGGCAAGACCAUGUUACUUGGAACUCUGGGGAAGAGAGGGGUGAUUCUUGAUUUUGUUUCACUAACAAAUUCUAAUGAAAACCUUUUUUCAUCUUUCAGUAACAAAUUCCAAAGCCCUUAAAUAAACGGAAAACAGACCAAAUUCUUCUAAAUAAGAACUAUCCCAGCUUACUUGUGAGUCUGCUUCUGCAUAUACUCGGACGACAUCUUCUGUACCAGAGGGCCGGACAAAAGCUCGAGAAAGCUUGUACUUCUUCACCAGGUCAUUGAUUGCCUCCUGUAAUCCUGGGGGUGUAACUGCUUGUCUUUCAGCAUCGGUAGUGCUAAUAACUCUCCUGUCUGCAACCUAAGUGCAAGCAUUUCAUAUUUGUUACUCUAUUACACUUCCUUUCAGAAGCUUAACCUGUUAAACAUACAUUCUACGAAAAGUGCCAGACUAAAUAUAAAAUUACAUUAAAACUUCUUUCUCCAAGGUCAGGGUAAUUAAUUUCAACAUUUGUGCAACUUUUCUCUUUUUCUUCAGUCUAUAAAGAAUUACCUUUGGCAAAAAAUAUUUCCACAAAUGCUUAGAGUUACCACUAAGAUAAUGGCCAGUAAAUACGAUAUGACUAAGUCCCAUAUCACACACAAAAACAGGAUAAGUGGUAGCCCAUUAUAUAAGAAGACCGAUAAGAAUUUCUUAAAUAUGCCAAAAAUAAUCUGAACAAUCAGCCAUUUCUGUGAACUGUGGCUUUAGUACCUCCAAUUGUCUUUCACAAAUUCUGUUGGUGAAUGUGUAAACUGGCAUAAACAUGUACAGAAAUCAAUUAGCAAUUUAUCUGAAUUCUCUCCCUCAGGAAGUACUCUGUGAACUAAACAUAAUGCAGAGUAAGUACUUUCACUUGAAAUGACAGGGCAUCUGAGUUUUGCUUCAAAAUAAUGUUGGGGCCAGGUGCAGUAGCUCACACCUGUAAUCCUAGCACUUUGGGAGGCCAAGGGAGAAGGAUCACCUGAGCUCAGGAGUUCAAGACCAGCCUAGGCAACAUAGUGAGAUCUCGUCUCUAAAUAAAAUAUACAAAAGAGUAUUGGGAGGGGGUAUGAAGAAUGUAUAGGGCAAUAAUUGAAAUCUGUUGAAGCUGGGUACACAAAAGUUCAUUAUGUUGUUUCUCUACAUUUAUAUCUAUUUUUAAUUUUUUUAUAUCUAUUUUUAAUUUUCCAUAAUAAAAUCUCUUUAAAAAA